GUUCCUGCCGGGCAGGACAGGUGCAUAGGGAACUCCUCAGAGGUCUGUACCUCGAGGGCUCCCAUGGAUAGCCUUGACAGAUCCUGCCAGGACUGGUGCGACAGGAAGCAACACUGGUUGGAGAUCGGACCACCGGACUUGGUGGAGCGCAAGGGCUCCCUGACCCUCCGCUCCCAUCACAAGAAAUACUCGAAGCCGGUGUUGGUGUAUUCCUGGCACCGUGACAGAGAAGCUUUUCCCAAAGGUUAUGAUAUAGAGGGUCCUGAGAAAGUUAAAAAACUGUGUAAUUCAACAUAUCGGCGACUGGGAACCGAUGAAUCCCCAAUUUGGACAUCAGAAACACAUGAAAAGUUGUCACAAAUGUGUUUAAACACAGAAUGGGUUGAAAUGAAGAGCAAGGCUUUAUUGAAUGAGGAAACAGUGAGCUCCGGGAUUAUCGAAAGGGUCACCGGAUUGCCUGCCACAGGUUUUGGAGCUGUCUUUCCUAGACAUCCACCGGAUUGGAGCAAAAUGUGUGCAUUGACAACGUACUCAGAAGAUUAUGUUCCACCAUAUGAUUAUCAGCCACAUGAAAGUUUCAAAAAUGGCACAAGGAGCUUCCAUAUAUUCUUUGCAGAGUUGAUAGCUGUUUACCAUAUGAAGGCUUAUCCCUGUCAAGAUGAUUAUUCCAUAGUCCACAGAAAAUGCCGUUCUCAGUUCACGGAUCUAAAUGGUUCUAAAAGAUUUGGCAUCAACACUUGGCAUGAUGAGAGUGGGAUUUAUGCUAAUUCAGAUGUAAAACAGAAACUCUAUCCCUUGACUAGUGGGCCUAUUGUGCCAAUUUAAAAAUAAUGUAUAGAAUCAGCAUCUCUGACUAAUGAAAAAUGGAUGUAGCAGUUGAUGAUUUUCUAUCUUAAUAAAUGCAAUGGAAGUGUUA